GCCAUCAAACUUGCAGACUUUUUUUACUCAGUUGCUCACUCUUCUGAGUCUAAAUAUCUAAUGGAGAUUUGGACUUUGUGUUCUGUUUAUUGUCCUCAGUAAUCUGAAGGACAAGCUUGCCUUCAACUCUCACAUAGUACAACCCUCAUUUAGACAGUUAACAGGUACUAUUAAAAUCUCCCAUAGGGCGGGAACUGGCAAUUGCAGCAAUAGACUUGGCUAUCAGAUUUCAUCAAAGGGAGCCUAAGGGCAGUGUGGCCAUGGAUGCCAGCACUCAUGGGGACAGACAGAGAGCAGGAGGAGGAGGCCUUGGUUUCCAAAAAGAGCCAUAGAAAGAACUCCGGGGAGUGGCUCUGCCCACUGUCUGAUGCUUGAAUCCUUACAUAACUGCUCUGAGAAAGGGCUUUUGCUUGGAUUUUUUCAGGGAUAAGGGAACAGGCUUUCUCCCAGAGUGAUCUGUUCUAUUUGGAACAGAUCUGUCUUUGAUAGAAAGUUCUUCCUUACACCUAGCAAAAAAUCAGCCCUCUUGACUCUCCACGUACUGAUCCUAGCCCUGCCUGACCUUUGAGGCCCCAAAUAACAAGUCUAAUCCAUGUGACAGCUUUUUUUUUUUUUUUUUUUUGAGACGGAGUCUCGCUCUGUCGCCCAGGCUGGAGUGCAGUGGCGCGAUCUCGGCUCACUGCAAGCUCCGCCUCCCGGGUUCACACCAUUCUCCUGCCUCAGCCUCCCGAGUAGCUGGGACUACAGGCGCCCGCUACCACGCCCGGCUAAUUUUUUGUAUUUUUAGUAGAGACGGCUUUUAAAGACAGUUUUUGUACCCCUCAAGUUGCUAGGUGGAACCUUCUCAGUGCUUUCAACCAUUCCUCAUUUAGUUGGUUUCCUACCCCUCUUGAUCCUAGUUCUGACCCCUGGAUAUACCACAAUUUGUCAUUAUCCCCUUUAUAGCAUGCUGCCUGGAAGAGAACACAUUAUCUGGCAAUUCUGAGUUGUGUAACAUGUACCCAUGUGUAACAUCUAGCAUGUAGAGUGGAUGGAGCAGAUGUCCACUUACUGGCCUGUAGAGUGGAUGGAGCCGAGGUCCACUUACUAGCAUGUGGGAUGGAUGGAGCCGAUGUCUACCCAUGAUUCUCUCAUGUCCUAAUGCAACCUAGAAUUGUGUUGGUUUAUUUGGCAUCUUGGAUUAUAUUAUUGCCUUCUGUUGAGCUUAUCAUCAACCAGAACUCCCAAGCAGAAUUUUUUUUUUCUGUUUUCAAUAUGCAUGCAGUUGCUUAGCCACAUCUUCCAUAUCCCGCAGGCUUAUUGGACCUUAAAUCUAUAGAUUUCAGCUUCUUGUUGAGAAGUUUUCUUAGCAAUAUUCUGCUGUGGGUAACUUCAGUUUUUAUACACAACAUAAAGAAGUCUCUCUGCAGUGUUUGAGAUAAAUUGAACAUCUGUACCAAGUAGACAACAGAGAGGUUUCUCGGUUGCUAGGGAAGGAUUGGGCAAUUAAUAAGUCCCUGUAUUCCAUCCUUUCACCUUCAGUAAUAUAUAGGUGUCAACCUAAAGGAAGAAGUUGAGACACAAAAUGCAAUUUUUAACAGUUUACUUGAACUGUUUACUUGAACCAAGUGAGGACAGCUGCCCGGGACACACUUCCAAGUUGCCUGGGGGAGUGCGUCCUUCGGCCUUUGUUACCACAGAUUCUUAAAGGCAAAAGCGAACAAGGAGAGGACUGAUACAAAGUGACUUGACAGGAAUUCUCAUCAGUUUACAGAAAUAGCAUGGAUUAUUGAUGGGCUGUACAUUGUUGGACUAUAGGGUAUGAGUUAUGAUGUCCAGUGUUAGCAUUUUAUGACUUAGUGGUGUCAGUUAGUCUAGAACCCACAUAGCAAGUGGCUUCAAGAGGUAAUUAUUUAACUCAAGGGGGGAGUGACACAUGACUGCUCUCACAUUUUAGUGCCUCUCUGGACCCGUAAUUUAAAGGGAUUCCUCAGAUAAAAAGUUUCUUUUCUUUCUCACAAGAUUCACUUGGAAGGUUCUAUCUUCAGAUGCUUUUGGUUUGUUGGAAGGGACUAGAAAUUGGCAGCUUUUUCUUUUUUUCAGUAGAGGCAGGGUCUCACUAUGGUGCCCAGGCUGGUCUUGAACUCCUGGGCCCAAGUGAUCCUCCCACCUCAGCCUCCCCAAAUGCUGGGAUUACAGGUGUGAGACACUGCACUCAGCUGCUGUUUGCAUAAAUAAUUAUGUUCAUUGACACCUAGAAUAUUAGUGCUAGAGGGAGUUGAGAGAUAUUUUAGUUUAUGCCCCAUGCUUUUUGCACAUUUGAAAAUGGUUCACAGGUACUAAGCAAACUGUUGACAGAGGUAGGCUUGGCGCCUGGGCCUCCUGACAUACCUGUAAACUGAUUUACGAGCUUAUACCUGUAUAGCAAGAGGUUACAAUGCUGGUAUUAAGAUACUUCAGAGAUUUUUUUUUUCUCCCGGCCCUCUAGUGAGUUUAAUUGCCCCAGAGCUGGUUGGCGUCCUUGAAUUCCUCUAGCUCAUGAGUAAAUGAAGCUCUCAUAGAUUUUUAGCCAAGUGGCUCUGGCAAUGAAGCUAGGCAGGAUCGUCUCUGGGAUUUCCAGGUCCUUUGCUGGCAUUUUGCCAGGUACUUCCCUUGUGAGAUAGCUUGGGGGUCCUUCCUACAUUGCAAUUGUUGAGAGAAAAUGCGAUCUCCCGUGGAUCUCUCUGGUGCCAGACUGGGGUGUUUCCAAAGGAGUACCCUGGCACUGGACCUAAGGAGAGCCUUCGGCGGAGCACCAUCCUCUGGCAGGUGGUGCUGGGUGUCGGGGCAGGGUGGGGUGCUGUGGCAGCAGUUGGAGGUCCUGUCUCCUCUCAAGGUAGCUGAGAUAGAGUGCCCAGGCUUAAGGUGGGCAUCCAGCCACAUGCCGGAGGACAGUCUGACGGGCAAGUAGCUGUGCCAGUCUGCCAAGUGUCGGGAGGAUUUUUGUCAUUUUUUAUAUUAAUGUACCCUUUUUUUGUCACUUGGUUCUUGAAGAGCAGGAAGUUGACUCUUUCACUGUGCUGUAAUACUCUCUCAUAGCAACUGGGACUCUGUAGAGUGGUUGUUUUCAGAUUCUGACAGGGGUCAGGAGAUAACGUUUUCUGCUUGGUACUACCUAGCUGUUGCAGGGCAGGUUACUUCAUCUUUUAGCAUUGAUUCUUCAUCUUUAAAGUAAGGGGCUUAGAGUGACCUGUGAAGGCUCAUUUAGCAAUGGUCUCUAGGAUUCUAGGGGCCUACAUCGCUCCCAAAAUGUGUCCUUAUUGUGUAUCUUUAAGAAGCCCUUGCUCUUCUCUUUUGUGUAGUAUUAAUAGUAUUCCUGAGUAAAUCCACCCAGGGGACACCACUCUCACCACCCUCCCAACACAUUGAAAGGACAUUUUUUUCUCUCACCAUUUUAAAAAUGAGCACAUCUAUAAAAAUAAAAAGGAAGAAGAGUUGUGGAUGGGAGAUGUUGAGACGAGGGCCAGGGUGAGCACCUUUCAGUUUCCUGGUCCUCCUCUGAGCUGCUUUCAGCUACCAUUUCUCAGUACUCAGGUUGGCAGCAAGAAAGGAGUCCCAGGGUCAGGGUAUAAGAGUUACUGGUGGCCUCCAGAGAGUAUAGGAUCAGCCUGUGGUCACAGCAGAGAGAAAGAGAACGGCAUGUGUGGCUCUGGGAUUUGGUGGGAGUUUCAGCAGAAUUGGAUGAUCCAGAGGGGAUUUCUGUUUUCUUUUUUUUUGUUGUUUGUUUGUUUUUUUUUUUGAGAUGGAGUUUCGCUCUUGUCGCCCAGGCUGGAGUGCAAUGGCACGAUCUCGGCUCACCACAACCUCCGCCUCCCGGUUUCAAGCGAUUCUCCUGCCUCAGCCUCCCGAGUAGCUGGGAUUACAGGCAUGCACCACCACGCCCGGCUAAUUUUGUAUUUUUAGUAGAGACGGGGUUUCUCCAUGUUACUCAGGCUGGUCUUGAACUCCGGACCUCAGGUGAUCCGCCCGCCUUGGCCUCCCAAAGUGCUGGGGUUGCAGGCGUGAGCCACCACACCCAGCCCAGAGAGGAUUUCUUGAGUGAAAUGUGUUCUCUAUUGAAGGCAGAGGAAAAAGAGUAUACGAUGAGAAAUACCCAGAUUUCCAUCCCCCCAAGAGCUUGUACAUAUAUAUAUAUACGUGUGUAUAUGUGUAUACGUGUAUAUAUAUACAUACACGUGUAUAUACGUAUAUAUAUAUAUAUAUAUAUGGGAUAUUUAUAUAUAUAUAUAUACACACACGAUUGAACUAUUGCACAAGGUCCAAGACAUUAUCUCAGAAAGGAGUAGAUAAUCCUGACCUAAGGAAUAGGGAAUGCGGAAUUCCAGGAAGCACUUCUCUUUCAUUUUCCCCCACUCCUCCCAAGCAGUGCCUCACUUCUGCCUUGUCUAGCUGUACUCCGGAAAAUUAAGAAAUUUAUGAGUGUAGCACCACGUAUACCAAUGGGAAGGAUGGGAGUCAGAAGUCAAGUGAACUCAGCCCGCCUCUGUGUACUUUGCACUUUUCCAUUUCCCUUGGUACCAGGCACUUUCAUACUUAAUCCAUAGUGGAGCUGUCACAGUGAGCAACUCUGACAAUGACAGCUUCUACCCCAGAGGCCACCCCAAAUAUGGAGCUAAAGGCUCCAGCUGCAGGAGGUCUUAAUGCUGGCCCUGUCCCCCCAGCUGCCAUGUCCACGCAGAGACUUCGGAAUGAAGACUACCACGACUACAGCUCCACGGACGUGAGCCCUGAGGAGAGCCCGUCGGAAGGCCUCAACAACCUCUCCUCCCCGGGCUCCUACCAGCGCUUUGGUCAAAGCAAUAGCACAACAUGGUUCCAGACCUUGAUCCACCUGUUAAAAGGCAACAUUGGCACAGGACUCCUGGGACUCCCUCUGGCGGUGAAAAAUGCAGGCAUCGUGAUGGGUCCCAUCAGCCUGCUGAUCAUAGGCAUCGUGGCCGUGCACUGCAUGGGUAUCCUGGUGAAAUGUGCUCACCACUUCUGCCGCAGGCUGAAUAAAUCCUUUGUGGAUUAUGGUGAUACUGUGAUGUAUGGACUAGAAUCCAGCCCCUGCUCCUGGCUCCGGAACCACGCACACUGGGGAAGACGUGUUGUGGACUUCUUCCUGAUUGUCACCCAGCUGGGAUUCUGCUGUGUCUAUUUUGUGUUUCUGGCUGACAACUUUAAACAGGUGAUAGAAGCGGCCAAUGGGACCACCAAUAACUGCCACAACAAUGAGACGGUGAUUCUGACGCCUACCAUGGACUCGCGACUCUACAUGCUCUCCUUCCUGCCCUUCCUGGUGCUGCUGGUUUUCAUCAGGAACCUCCGAGCCCUGUCCAUCUUCUCCCUGUUGGCCAACAUCACCAUGCUGGUCAGCUUGGUCAUGAUCUACCAGUUCAUUGUUCAGAGGAUCCCAGACCCCAGCCACCUCCCCUUGGUGGCCCCUUGGAAGACCUACCCUCUCUUCUUUGGCACAGCGAUUUUUUCAUUUGAAGGCAUUGGAAUGGUUCUGCCCCUGGAAAACAAAAUGAAGGAUCCUCGGAAGUUCCCACUCAUCCUGUACCUGGGCAUGGUCAUCGUCACCAUCCUCUACAUCAGCCUGGGGUGUCUGGGGUACCUGCAAUUUGGAGCUAAUAUCCAAGGCAGCAUAACCCUCAACCUGCCCAACUGCUGGUUGUACCAGUCAGUUAAGCUGCUGUACUCCAUCGGGAUCUUUUUCACCUACGCACUCCAGUUCUACGUCCCGGCUGAGAUCAUCAUCCCCUUCUUUGUGUCCCGAGCGCCCGAGCACUGUGAGUUAGUGGUGGACCUGUUUGUGCGCACAGUGCUGGUCUGCCUGACAUAUGCCUCUUGGAUUUUGCUUCACUUUUCCUGGCCCUGUCUGUGAGUCUCAUCUCCCUUCAACAGGACGAUGCUCAGAAGACACGGCUGCUUUUGGUCUUCAAGUGUGUGCAGUUGUUUUUCCCUUCUGUGAUCUGUUGUGACUUAGCAUUGCAUUGUCAUCCUGUUCAAAAAGGCAGCCCCCUUUAUGUCUGAGAGCACUCGCCUCUCUCACCUUCCUUGGAGACUUUGAAGUAAUUGUGGGACUCAGUAGAGGCCUUUCAUGGCAGCAGCAACUUAAAUGUAUUUAUGCGCGUUCAUUUUGUUCUUGCUUCUCUGUUCUUUCAGAUCUUUCAGCACCGUUGGUUAGUAUGUGAUUUUAGAUCUUUAAUUGAUUUUUUUCAUUUAUAUUCAUAAAUUUUAACAGCAGCUUCUUUUAUUACUAUUUCUGGUGUUUUCCUAUCUUUUCCCCAACUUUUCCUCCUCCUCUUCACCCUCCAAAGGGAACAGGAGGAAUUCAGUGUAGUUUCUUUUUUUUUUUCCCUCUUGGAAUUCAACUUUCUCACCACUCUCCCCCAUCCUCCAAAGAUUACUAUGGCUGAUACGGACUUUGUGAUGCUUAAUUUCAAACAGUUGGAGAAGAGGGGGAGGGAAAACAAGUAUUUCAUAGGAUAGUGCUCAUUUUGUUAUGAUUUCAUAUCGGACAGUAUCUACUUCCAGCCCAUAUUUUUGGAAAUGCGGACUUAGCAGGUCACCUUAUGUCCAGACCUUGUGUGGAAGAGGCUGGCCCCACCUGUGGAGUCUGGAGUUGUAGGAUCAACGGUUUUUUAGAUUUCUUUGGAGCAAUAACCCAUCCAUCCUUCAGUGAUUCAUACUGAUUCUCUGUGUCAUUUGCCAUGUGAAACAUUUUACUUCAGUUUGCUAUGAAAAUUUCAGAAACCUAUUUCUGAAGAUAUAAUUACCUAAAAUCGCAUCAUCCAAGAAGCCUGUUCAGACUGGAAUGCAGAGCUGCAAAACAUUCCAAGCAGUCGGAUUUUUAGAGGAUGAAGCUUCCAGGUCCAAACAGAGUAGCUUCUUAGUACCUUUGGGCCUUUCACACUUUUUAGUCUUGCAGCUACAGUGAAGAAGAGCAGCAUCAUUAAUUAGCUGUGUAACCCUGCCACCCCCCACCCUGCAUUCCCCGCCCAGGAACCCUCAUAAGGCCUCAGGGUCCUCAACUGUAAGAUAGGAAGGGUGUCUGACCUCUAAGGUUUCUCUCAACUCCAAAAUUCUGUGAUUCUGUAUAGGUGCUUUGCGCUUGAUUUUAAGUUUCUACACAAAUAUUACUCUAAAAAAAGAAAGUCAAUGUAAAAACAUUUGGGAAUAAAAGAAGAAAUUCCAGUAUUCCACCAAUUUAACAAAGUAAUUUUUUUUUGCAUUGUAUCUUCUGUGUCUUAAUCCUCAUGGGUGCCUUGUAAAAAUAGUUGCAAUUGUAGUUUACACAUAAUUUUGUCUUUCACAUUUUAUUUAGUUUUAUAUCACAAAUAUUCAUAUCUUUCACUAAUAUUUUCAUGACCUCGUGGUAUUCCACUGUAUUGGUGGAUCAUAUUAACUAAGGUACUCCUUUCAUGUUGGACAUGGUGGUUGUUUCCCUUGUUUUCGUAUUUUUUAAAUUUAUACCCCCACUAAGUCAAACUUUGUAUACUGUCCAAGACUACUAUGAAUUUUAAAGGCAUAUUUAUAGACAUUUAAAAGUAACAUGGUGAAACCCCGUCUCUACUAAAAAUACAAAAACAAAAUUAGCCUGGUGUGGUGGCAGGUGCCUGUAGUCCCAGCUACUUGGGAGGCUGAGGCAGGAGAAUGGCAUGAACCCAGGAGGCAGAGCUUGCAGUGAGCCAAGAUCGCGCCACUGCACUCCAGCCUAGGUGACAGGGCGAGACUCCAUCUCAAAAACAAUAAAAAUAAAAAUAAAAAUAAAUAAAUAAAAGUAACUUGGUAAGUUUUAACAGCUUUGAUCAUAAUAAAAUAGCAGCAAGAGCUCCCAGCACAGGAGCCAUAAAUGGCCAGCGUAUUUCGUAAGUUCGCUUUUGUUCUUUUCAGUGCUUUGCUCUUGUUGUGUAUAAGUCAGCUCUUUCUGAUGCUGGUUCAAAACCACAGGCUCCAGAAUCCAGUUCCUUCUGUGAACAUGACUGUUGGCCUUAUGUUGCUUCAGCAGUUUAAAAGCUCAUAUUCUUUGUGUCUCUUGACUCGAAGGGAAGAUGUUUUGUAAUACUGUUGGAGCCCUCUUGACUAAUCAUGUGGUCGAGCUGAGGUUGUCCUCUGUCCCCCCUUUUGUACACGCCACAGCUGAGCUGCUGCUGAGAAGUGUAUAACUGCAUUUGUUAUACAAAUGUCUUCCUUUUUGUCUGGGCUGGGGUCUUUGUGUGUGUGGGGGGGGUGAUUAGGGGAGAGUAGGGAGAGGGCUGUUCCUGGCUGGCUGCUUCCUGAGAUAUCUACCUUGUUGAGUGUCUCUUCAUAGGCACUUUAACUCACAGAAGACAUUUAGUGCCAGAAGGGGUUUUAUUUGCCCCACAUGUCUGCAUAGUCGAUUGCUGCUUCUGGAGUUAGUUAAAGUCAUUUUCCAUGGUGGCAAAACAGAUACCCGUGCUGUUGAACCCUGGGGGCUGCUGAUGCUGAUUUGGUUUGGACAUCCUUCUCUUCUUCCCACUUUGUGUUAGUGGGAGGCUCGCUCUUCUUGCCCUCUGCAGUGUCACGCUUCAUGUAGGGUUCAGCGGUGGUAUGUGGUUCAGCUAGGACAGGAAGAAGGACUUCCCUUUGCAGCCCUGUGGUCCUGGCUUUAAGAGGAGAGAAAUGUUCUUAAAAUCUCUAUUAAGGAUAUUUUUAUUAGGCAUGUUUAUCUUAUAUAGUGGUGAAAACAAGAACAAGUUUUUAGAUUACUUAUAAAAUAUCAUGAUGAAGCGGAAGAUCUUUGUCCAAUCAGAGGAAAAAUUCUGAUCCCAAUCUUCUGUUUCUGUUUCCACUUAACUCCCACCACAGAGUGGAGCAUCUCUCUGACUCCACUUAACUAUCAUGAAGUGCCCAUAUGUCCUGCUAGGUCAGUAUGGGAGAGGGUGGGGAGAUGACAGACUCUCAGGGCUGGGAAAGGCUCUGAUUUGUCUCCUGCCAGGGACUCAUUUUCUCUGAUAAUAAAGGCCUCCUGUCUCUUGAGCGGACAUCAGCAUUUGUGGAGAUGCUUGUGUGGCUGGGACUGAAGGAAUAACUCACACUUCCUUUAUCCAUACAAAACCGAGUGGGUUAGAAGCUCCCUUUUGGGCAAGCCAUGUGUUCGAGGCUUGGAGCCCCAUCGCUUUGCUGUGCCACCCUCAGGCAGGACGUGGUGCUUCCCAGUUGUCAGUGAGGUGAGGAACAUAUCCCAGAACACAGUCCUAAGUGACUAACACUGGAGUGUAUAGUUCCUUAGAAUUUCAGAGUUGGGCGAGACUUCAGACAUCACCCAGUUACCACAUUUCACAGGUAAACGAAUGAACUGAGGCUCAGAAUAGUAAGCUGAUUUGCCCUGCACCACUCAGCUUGUUAUGGAGCAGGGACUGGUGAUAAUAUUGAAGCAUUUAUUAUUGGUUUUUAGAACGCUGAGUUCUUUACAUGAGUGAUAUCGUUUGACCAUCCUGUUUAGUAGUUGGGGAAAUGAGUCUCAAAGAGUUUAGGUAACUAGCCACUGAGUGGUAGAGCUGAGGUUGGAGCCUGGGCAUUCCAAAUCCAGAGCCUACACCCAUUCCUAUACCACCCUCUCCCUGGGGCUCAGUUCUCCCGAUUGUUACCUCAGUGCAGCUUCCACCCCACAGUAACACCUGGCACCAUCACUGCAAGGAUGACAUUAGGCAGGGAGACCCAGACCCCAGAGAGGGCAAGUGUCUUGGUGUCGGUACCACAGCAGACCAGCUCUUUUGUUGAGCGUUAGAUGACCUAUGAUGAGAAUGCUGUUUUGUCAUCAGCCUACAAUUUUACCUCCAAUUUUCUCCAUAUUCAACCCUCAAGGUUUGGGGGAUGUCACCAACUCUAUUUAGAAGCAGCUAAGGGCUGAAAACAUAGUAGUUUUGAGUUUCAGGGAAAUUAAAAGCCUAAACUUUUUGCACACUUCUCAAAGCCUUGAGAUCGGUGAAGAUGUUAAUGAGAAUUGCCAUUAUGGUUGAUUAAUAGAAGAAGGAAAGAUGAAGAACUGCCCCAGAGUAUAUAACACUGUGGCAGAGGUGGAUCUGAGACUCGAUAUCCUUGUACCCGUUUGCUGUCAGGCUUUGGAUCCCUUGUCCAAUUCCACUUGACAAAGCAGAAAGAGGUCAGGGCUGAUCGUGUGCUGGGUUCUCCACCAUGCACCAUGGUGCAUCCCUGUGAAAGCUAGCCUGGGUAUCUACCUCUCAUUUCCUCACAGGCAGGAUCCUUCCACUGAUCCGCCAGACUCCCUGUCUCCCCUCCCUCUGCAUUUCCUUGCCCAUCAGGUCUGUGAGGUUAUGGGCCAGGGGCUUGAGGUCCUGGAUCCUGGUCCCAGCUCUGUUGCUUCCUGUCGUUUACACCCUCUGGGCCUCUCUUUCCAUAGGACUGUAGUAAUAUUGUGGAGUUACAUACCUGUGAAACAGAGGCAGAUUCACCUCCACUAGUGAGUGCUUAGCAGUGCUCUCUGCUGGGUACCACUAGACAUUCUGCAGUAAUGGAAAUGAAUGGAAAUGUCCCAUGUGUGUGCUGUCCAUUGCAGCAGCCACUAGGCACCAGUGGUUGUUGAGCCUUUGAAAUGUGGCUAGUGUGAAUGAAGAACAGGAUUUAAUUUCAUUUUAAUUCAUUUCAAUGUAAAUAGCCGUCCGUGGCUAUGUUGGACAGCACAGCUCCAGGGUAAGUGUGAGGCAGGAGGCAUGAAUCCAUUCUUUCCCUGGUGUGUUAGUCCAUUUGCGUUGUUAUAAAGAAGCACCUGAGACUGGGUAAUUUAUAAAGAAAAGAGGUUUAUUUUGGCUCAUGGCUCUGCAGGCUGUACAGGAAGUGUGAUGCCAGCAUCUGCUUCUGGUGAGGGCCUCAGGAAGCUUCUAAUCAUGGCAGAAGGCAAAGGGGGAGCAGGCUUUAUAUGGCAAGACAGGGAGCAAGGAGAAGGGAGGUACCAGGCUCUUUUAAACAACAGCUCUCUCAGGGAGGGCCCCAAGUCAUUCAUGAGGGAUUUGCCCCCACGACUCAAACACUUCCCACCAGGCCCCACCUCUGACAUUGGGGAUCACAUUUCAACAUGAAAUUUGGAGGGGAUCCAAACCAUAUUACCUGGUAAGUCCUUGUUUCCACAUGUCUCUCAUCUUACUGCAGGGAGUGCUAUUCUCUUUUGUUUGUUUUUAUGGCUCCUCAAAAAUCAACUUUAGACAUUUCAGUUUAAAGUGUUUCUUAAAAAUCUGGUCUCUAAAUGCAAUCCAAUCCUUCAGCUGCUCAGCCAAAGAAGCAGUGAUCGAUGUAGACAUUGGCUGCCUUGGACUGAGAUGUUCUGGCAGUCUCACCAGUGUGGUGCCUUCCUUAGAGUGACUUGACUGCAUUUUCGCUUUACAGAAUGAACUUAGAAGCAAACCUCUCAUAUAAAAUGUAACCCUCUCGUAGGAAUCAAUGAGGUAGUAGAUAAGCUCUGGAUGUCUGUAUCAAGGCUGGGAGCAUCCAGCUGUAGCCCAGCAGUAGGAAAGACAAUCUGUCAAACUAUAUUUGAUUGCUAACAGGUUAGUAACUAACAGGAAGUCAUGCACUGUAGCAGGAUGUACUUUUCAUGGCCAAAAAGAUGAGUACUAAUGAUGAUAACAUUAACAGGUAAGACAUCCCUACUGUACACCAGGCCUUUUGUGAGGCACCUGCAUAACCUCAUUUGACCAUCAUGACAUCUCUAUGAUUCAGGAGCAGUUAAUAUCCCCAUUUUGCCAACAAGAAAACUGGGGAAUAGAAAGGUACCAUACCUUCCCCAAUGUCACUCAGCUAAUUAGCAGCAGAGCCAGGAUCUGAACACAAGAACCUAGUUCCAGAGCCCACAGGCCUCAAUAAACCUGUGAAACACUGGCCUUUGCCCACCUGGUGGAAAGAUCGGUGAGAUGGGAAGCGUGGGGUCAGUGGGCACUAGGAUGGGUGUAUUCGGUGAAGCCUCCUCCUGCUUACAGCACUGUCUGGCAGUGUUGACAAUGGCUGGUAUGGCACGGAAGCCGAUGGCACCUCCUGCGGCAGUGCACCAUUGGUCUUCGUCAGUUCCUCCUUCCUGGCUCACCCGUGGCUGAGUUUCAGAUGUGAGAGCCAGUGGGUGUCCUGUCACAGAGAUACGGUCGUCGUGUGGGGCUUCGCCAGGGGUCAGCCUGCAGAUAGAACUGCUUUUUUUCACCUGUAUCAAAAUGCUCUGUGAAAUGCGGUUUUAUCACGGUGUCUUUCCAGAAGGCGGGGUUUCUUUUCCUAUUUGGUUUCUUGUCAGUCAGGUAGAGAUGUUUGUGUUGGAGGCUCCCUGAGUGGUAAGAAAAUGAGCAGCUGCUCAGGAACGUCCACCUCCUUUUCUUCUCCCUACCCUCCCUCCUUGGGUAGAAACCAGAUUGACCUGAAAUGUAAUUUGGUUCCUUUUGCACAGAAAGAUGGAAGUCAUGUGCUGUAGCCGGAAAAGCUGAAAGCCUGGGGACCGGAGCCAGAAGAUCCGGGUUCCGGUCCCAGUUCUGCUGACCUUGCAGUGGGACGCCAGUUAUUCCAUGUUUCUGGGCAUCUAUUUCACAGAGAUUGAACUGGACAAUGUCUAAGUUUUCUUAGAGCUCUCAAUCCUAUAAGAUGGACAGAUGCUGAAUUCGCUCAACAGUAGGGAGACAGACCUUUCCCAGCUCUGGGCAUCUUAAACAGGCAUGUCCUCUCU